GGAUGUUUACGGCGGCCGAGGUUGGAGCGGCGCUGCUCGGCCGCGGACACACGAGGGACGCGCCCGAGGAGCUGCAGGUGGCAGCCCAGGCGGUCCGAACCCGUCGGCCGGCCGAGCCUGGAGUAUUGCCUAAGUGUAAUCUUGAACAUGGGCGGUGCUGUGAGUGCUGGUGAAGACAAUGAUGAGCUGAUAGAUAAUUUGAAAGAAGCACAGUAUAUCCGGACUGAGCUGGUAGAGCAGGCUUUCAGAGCUAUCGAUCGUGCAGACUAUUAUCUUGAAGAAUUUAAAGAAAAUGCUUAUAAAGACUUGGCAUGGAAGCAUGGAAACAUUCACCUCUCAGCCCCGUGCAUCUACUCGGAGGUGAUGGAAGCCCUAGAUCUGCAGCCUGGACUCUCGUUUCUGAACCUGGGCAGUGGCACUGGGUAUCUCAGCUCCAUGGUGGGCCUCAUUCUAGGUCCUUUUGGUGUGAACCAUGGGGUGGAACUUCACUCAGAUGUGAUAGAGUAUGCAAAGCAGAAACUGGACUUCUUCAUCAGAACAAGUGAUAGUUUUGACAAGUUUGACUUCUGUGAACCUUCCUUUGUUACUGGGAAUUGCCUGGAGAUUUCUCCGGAUUGUUCUCAGUAUGAUCGUGUAUACUGUGGGGCUGGCGUGCAGAAAGAGCAUGAAGAGUACAUGAAGAAUCUUCUCAAAGUGGGAGGGAUCCUUGUCAUGCCACUGGAAGAGAAGUUGACUAAGAUAACACGCACAGGUCCUUCAGCUUGGGAAACCAAAAAGAUUCUUGCUGUUUCUUUUGCUCCUCUGAUCCAGCCCUGCCAUUCAGAGUCAGGAAAAUCAAGACUUGUCCAGUUACCACCAGUGGCAGUUCGCAGCCUCCAGGACUUGGCUCGCAUCGCCAUCCGGGGCACCAUUAAAAAGAUUAUUCAUCAGGAAACUGUGAGCAAAAACGGAAACGGACUAAAGAACACCCCCAGGUUUAAACGAAGGAGAGUUCGCCGCCGUCGAAUGGAAACGAUUGUCUUUUUGGACAAAGAAGUCUUUGCCAGUCGGAUUUCCAACCCCUCAGAUGACAACAGCUGUGAAGACUUGGAAGAGGAACGGAGGGAAGAAGAAGAGAAGACCCCGCCGGAAACAAAGCCAGACCCCCCAGUGAACUUCCUACGCCAGAAGGUCCUGAGCCUCCCUCUGCCAGAUCCCCUGAAAUACUACUUGCUUUAUUACAGAGAAAAAUAAGUCUCCUGUUUGAAAGGGGGAAAUAGGAAGAGCAGAUUGCUGAGUGUGAAGUUCGUGCUGCCUGUGUGCUGUUGAAGGGUCACCUGGAGGCAGACGUUGUGGGGAAGGGAACUGCUGGGCUCAUCCACACCAUGGUUUUCUUCUAGUUCCUGAUUGACCUCUAAAAUUCUAUUCAGUUGUAUGAUUUGUUUACAUAGUUCCACAAGACCUUCAUUGCAUAGAAGAUUGUUUUCCCAAAGUGGAGAGAAUCUUCAUAGAGAAAAAGAGAAGGCUGUUUCUUUUUCGGCUCUGACGAAACACUGAAGUCUGCGUAAGAGAGACUGUUUGAUGACCGUCCCUCAUGCAACAUGCACGGUACUCACUAAAAAUGAAAACUGAAGUGGAAACUAACCUGUGUUGCUUAUAAAGUGUGAAAGCACAAGCUUAUAAAUGUAUAAAAUCUUUUCUGGGUGUGACGCACCUGCGUCCAAGUUUGAAUUUUUAUGAUAUGUACCACUUAAUUACUGGCACUGAGUAUCACUGAAUUUCUUAGUUUUCUAGUGGGGAAACAUUAUUGAGAAGCCCUCCCUUAUUUUAAGUAAGUUGAUUAAAUCUUAUGUGAGUUGCCAGUUGUAAUUUUUCAAAGGAAAAAUUUUGAUGGGGUGGAGGAAUGAAUUGCCAGAUAAUCUUUCUGGAAUUCCGAGAGAAUUCCAAAGAGGGUUUUUUUUUUUUUUUUUAGGACAUCUUUUGAUACCUUUAAAAGAACCACUGUCAAGUAAUCCUUAAAAGAAUAUCUUGGAAAAGGAAACAGAUUUUUUCCUGUGUGUAAGCAAUAAGUGAAGUUACAUUUGCCCUAACCCUAGGGAUGAUUCUUUACCCAGUUUUAAAGCCCAUCAUGGUAUUCUAAGGUGUUGACACCCUCCAUCCUCAGAGCAGGUCGAAAAUAUUAAAUAGACUGGGGACUCUAUGAUGGGCAGCCUGUGCUUUUUGACUUCAGUUUGCUAUUUUUCUGUGAUCACAUUAGUACUGAUUCAUAGAUUCUAUCUUUUAUAAUUCUGGAGAAAAAGAUUUGUUAGUUUUGUAAUUUUUUUGUAAGACCAAAUGUAUGUAUUUUAGUAGCUCCAUUGCAUGAGAAGAGUGUAACUCACACUGACUUGUGAUAUCAGCCUUCUCUGGGCCUUGUGUGUGGAGAGCUUUCUAUCUUACCAAGUGGUAGGGCUAAAAGAACAACAGCCUUUUUGGUAGUCACAUAGCAGAAUGAUC